ACACUGAAGCUGAGAGCCUCCCAAAGUGCUGGCUACCUGCUGAGCGCCCCCGUAACUCUGACACAGUAGUAAUUUGAGCCUCUGCAAUUGCCGUCUGCUUCCUGUGAAAGUCCUUUCCGUGCCCACUGACCCUUGAGUGGGCCUUUGAGCUGCUGACUUUCAGCUGGAACUUGAAGGGACCCCAACCCUGAGACACUAUGGCCCUGACCUCAGACCUGGGGAAACAGAUAAAACUGAAAGAGGUGGAGGGGACCCUCCUGCAGCCUGCAACUGUGGACAACUGGAGCCAGAUCCAGAGCUUCGAGGCCAAACCAGAUGAUCUCCUCAUCUGCACCUACCCUAAAGCAGGGACAACGUGGAUUCAGGAAAUUGUGGAUAUGAUUGAACAGAAUGGGGACGUGGAGAAGUGCCAGCGAGCCAUCAUCCAACACCGCCAUCCUUUCAUUGAGUGGGCUCGGCCACCCCAACCUUCUGAGACAGGAUUUCACCAUGUUGCCCAGGCUGGUCUCAAACUCCUGAGCUCAAGCAAUCCACCUGCCUCAACCUCCCAAAGUGCCAAGAUUACAGACCUGCUGCCACCGUCUUUCUGGGAAAACAACUGCAAGUUCCUUUAUGUAGCUCGAAAUGCCAAAGACUGUAUGGUUUCCUACUACCAUUUCCAAAGGAUGAACCACAUGCUUCCUGACCCUGGUACCUGGGAAGAGUAUUUUGAAACCUUCAUCAAUGGAAAAGUGGUUUGGGGUUCCUGGUUUGACCACGUGAAAGGAUGGUGGGAGAUGAAAGACAGACACCAGAUUCUCUUCCUCUUCUAUGAGGACAUAAAGAGGGACCCAAAGCAUGAAAUUCGGAAGGUGAUGCAGUUCAUGGGAAAGAAGGUGGAUGAAACAGUGCUAGAUAAAAUUGUCCAGGAGACGUCAUUUGAGAAAAUGAAAGAAAAUCCCAUGACAAAUCGUUCUACAGUUUCCAAAUCUAUCUUGGACCAGUCAAUUUCCUCCUUCAUGAGAAAAGGAACUGUGGGGGAUUGGAAAAACCACUUCACUGUUGCCCAGAAUGAGAGGUUUGAUGAAAUCUAUAGAAGAAAGAUGGAAGGAACCUCCAUAAACUUCUGCAUGGAACUCUGAGCAAGAUGUAAAUAAAAUUAAAAGGUGGAUGGCAAGAGUGCAAAUACUAUCUUCAAUCCUUCAGUCCCAGCCAGAAGAAUCUCUGAAAGCAUAUUGUGAAUGUAUACAAUGUAGUACAAACAAUCUCUGUGAUGAUUAACAGUAUGUCACCACUUCAUUUUUUAAAAAGGAUCACGUCUAAUGCCCAUUUUCCCAACUAUUCUUUCCAAAGUAAGAUAUAAGGUAGCUUAAUAAACUAAGUAAAACGUAUGACUUGAGUACAAAAGGAUUGUUUUAAUCCCCAUUAUUCUGGAAAGUGCAUCCUAGUCUCCCAGUCUAUAACAUCAUAAUACCUUGAGUAUAAGUCCAAAUAUUAGGUUAUAUCUAUAUUAAAAACAAAAUUUCUGUCAUCUGUCCUGGCCAUUCAGGCAACUCCAGCCUGGGCUCAAUCCUGGAGUUCUGUCUGGUCACUAUCAGAAGGAACACUUUGAGGGAAACCCUGGUGCAGCCAGCCCUGAGGAAACAUGGCCUGAGUGCCCUCACUGGUGGGUGGGAAUAAAAUGGAAGUGCACAGAGGAGAUGUCAGAAGACCAAAACUUGGUGAAUAGUCCCAGUGCUAGGUCAUAUAGGAAACAGAAAGCAUGACAGUGGCCUUUUGGGAACCCAAGUUACGUCCUGGUGAAAGCAGAAAGGAGGAGACAGGAUGGCUGUCAACAACGUCAGCAUGGGCAUGGCUCCCAGGCAUGGAGGUAAUUGGGUCUUGGCUUCAAUGCCACCCUUUUGGGAAGCCCUAAACCAAGUGAGGUGUUCUUUUCCCUUGCUUCCCAUAUUUGUCCCAGUUGCAGCCCUGUUGUUAUGUAUUUACUCUUCAAUUUCUUAUUUAUACCUCUCACUCAAUUGUUAAUUCUUUGGGUUCAGUCUCAUGCCAUAUUUACUCCUAGUACCUAAUGCAGUGCCUGGCACACAGCAAGUGCCCUUGAGAACUUGUAGAGGGAGUAAAAAAGUGCAUGGAUAAAUGACUGCAGCAAAUCACAAAUUUUGAACUUUGACCCUUUUCUUUUAGUCCCAAAUAGUGGCAUUCCAUAGCUGAGGGUAGUAGGAGCAGUUCACCCUGGGAGCAGACAAUAAGAGGAAGAAUGAAGCCAACUAAAAUUCUGAAUGCUUUUUGUUGGAUUUCGUAGGGUAUUUUUUUUAAAAUAGGGUCUUGCUAUGUUGCCCAGGCUGGUCUUAACUGACUGCUUUUUAUUAUUACCAUGCACUGGCAAUUCCAAACAAUGUCAGUGUUAAAAUGCUUCUCCCUGAAAAAGAGAAAAAAAAAAGGAAAAAAAGAAAAGAAAAGUGAAAAGAAAAACUCUUAUUGGCCUAAGUUCUAAAUAAUAGCUAGGUUACCACUGAGUUUUAACUAUAUGUAUAUGAGCUUCAAAUAAGCACCUUUUUAUUAUGUAAAUAAAUAAAAGUUAUCUGUAUCCCCA